AGAGACAGGGUCUUAUUCUGUCGUCUAGGCCUCAGCUCCUGGCCUCAAGCGAUCCUCUCCCCUCAGCCUCCCCAAGUAUUGGGAUUGCAGGUGUGAGCCAGGACGCCUACCCGCAAACAGAAACUCUUUACCCAUUAAACAAUAACUCUGUAGUAUUCCUUCCUUCCUGCCCCUGGUAACCACUAUAGUACUUUCUGUCUAAUAUGAAUUUGCCUGUUCGAGGUGCCUCAUAUAGGUGGAAUUGCAUAUUUGUGCCUGGCAUAUUUCAUUUAGCACAUUUUUUCAAGGCUCAUCCAUAUAGCACGUAUCAGUACUUCAUUUCUUUUAGUUGCUGAAUAUUAUUAUUAUUAUUAUUUUUGAGACAGAGUCUCACUCUGUCUCUUAGGCUAGAGUGCAGUAGCAUGAUCUCGGCUCACUGCAACCUCCGCCUCCCGGGUUCAAGCGAUUCUUGUGUCUCAGCUUCCCGAGUAGCUGAGAUUACAGGCGCCCACCACCACGCCCGACUAAUUUUUGUAUUAUUAUUAUUUUUUAGUAGAGACAGGGUUUCACCAUGUUGGCCAGGCUGGUCUUGAACUACUGACCUCAGGUGAUCCACCCGCCUCAGUCUCCCAAAGUGCUGGGAUUACAGGCGUGAGCCAACACGCCUGGCUGCUGAAUAUUAUUUUAUUGUGUAGAGUAAUGUAUUCAUUCGUUGGUUGAUAAGGCAUUUGGGUUAUUUUCACCUUUUGGCUGUUGUUCCAGAUAAUGCUGCUAUGAGCAUAUUUGUACAGGUUUUUGUGUGGAAAUAUGUUUUUGUUUCUCUUCGGUAUAUAGGAAAAGAAUUACAGAAUCAACUCUGUGCUUAACCAUUUGAAGAACUGGUUUUCUUUUCCAAAAUGGCUGCACCAUUUACAGCCCUGCCAGCAGGUUAUAAAAGUUCCAGCUUCUCUGCAUCCUUGGCAACAUUUGUUAUUAUUUUUUUAUUAUAGCCACUCAGGUGGGUCUGAAGUAUUUUGUCGUGUUUUUUAUUUGUGUUUCCUUGUUACUGAUAUCGUUCAGCAUAUUUCCAUGUGCUUAUUGCUCAUAUGCAUAUGUUCUUUGGAGAACUGUCUGAGAUUCUUUGCUCAUUUUUAACUGGGUUAUUUCUCUUUUUAUUGUUGAAUUUCAAUGGUUCUUUAUAUAUUCCAGAUACAAGUCCUUAUCAGUUACAUGAUUUACAAAAAUUUUCUACCAUUCCCAUUCCUUGAGUUGUCUUUUCACUUUCUUGAUGGUGCCCUUUGAAGCACAACAUUUGUGUGUGUGUGUGUGUGUAUUUUUAGUAGAGAUGGGGUUUUGCCAUGUUGGUCGGGCGGGUCUUAAACUCCUGAUCUCAGGUGAUCCACCCACCUUGCCGGUGAACCACCACAGCACCCGGCCCGUUUUUGGUUUUUUUGUUUGUUUGUUUUUUGAGCCAGAGUAUUGCUCUGUUGCCCUGGCUGGAGUGCCGUAGUGCCAUCUUGGUUCACGGCAACAUCUGGCUCCCGGGUUCAAGUGAUUCUUCUGCCUCAGCCUCCCGAGUAGCUGGGAUUACAGGUACACACCACCACACCCUGCUAAUUUUUAUAUUUUUGGUAGAGACAGAGUUUUGCCAUGUUCCUCAGGCUGGUCUCAAACUCCUGAAUUCAAGUGAUCCACCCGCCUCAGCCUCCCAAAGUGCUGGGAUUACAGGCGUGAGCCACCACUCCCGGCCAGAAGCACAAUUUUUAAUUUUUAUGAUGUUCAGUUUAUAUUUGUUUUUCCCUUUGUUGCUUGUAUUUUUGUGUGUCUUAAUAUGUCUUCUAAGUCUGUUUUAAUGGAUGGAUUCUCCCCUUCCUGCCUCUCAUUUAUCUGUUGAAGAAUUUUGCCUAUUUGACCUGUAGAGUUUCCUAUGGUCUGGAUUUUUCUAAUUAUGUUCCCAUGGUACAGUUCAGCUUCUCUCUGUCUCUGUAUUUCCUGCAAAUUGGCAGCUACACCAAGAGGUGUGAUCAGAUUCUGAUGUUCAAGGGCUUUUGUCUAUCUUACAGGCAGUCAGUAUGCUAUUAUAUUAGGAGACACACAAUGUGUGGUUGUGUCUCUGUGAUAUUAUUUUAGUAGCUUUGAUGCUGAAUGCUGAUUAGGUCUUCAUUGGGGUUUGCAAAUGUAUGAUAGUCUAAUUCUGUUAUCAUUUGUUAGCUGACAAACUUUUGUUUAAAUUUUAUUUUAAAAAUUAAUAAAAGCAGGGACAGGAGGAUCGCUUGAGCCCAGGAAUUGAAGACCACCCUGGUCAACAUAGUGAGACAUCAUUUGUACAAAAAAUUAGAAAAAUUAGCCAGGCGUGGUGGUGUCAACCUGUAGUCCUGGCUGUUCGGGAGGCUGAGAUGAGAGGAUUGUUUGAGCCCAGGAAUUUGAGGGUUGUGGUAAGCUCUGAGCAUGCCACUGCUCUCCAGGGCAAAAAAGAAAAAAAAAAACCCUAAAAAUAGAGCUUUUGGGGAUAUACAGUUCUAUGAAUUUUAACACAUCUAUAGAUAUAACAAACUACAAGUCAUUAUACAGAGCAGUUCAGUCACCGGAAAACCUCCUGCUAUCCCUUUGCAGUCACACCCCUACUUCACCCCAACUCUGGAAACCAGCAACCUGUUUCCUGUCACUCUAGUUUUGUCUUUUUGAAGUACCCUCUUGAGACUGUGUUAUUUAGCAUUAUGCCUUUUGAGGGUCAUCCAGGUUGUUGCAUGUGUGAAGAGUGUUGUCCCUUUCUGUGGUUGAUUAUCAUUCCAUUGGAUGGAUGUGCCAGUUUUUUAUUCGUUCACUUUUAGAAGGACUUACGUGUUGUGUCCAGUUUUUGGCGAUGAUGAAUAGAGCUGCUCUAUACAUUCAUGUAUACAUUUCUUGCUUGCACAUAGGUUACAUUUCACCAGCUAAGUACCUAGGAAUGGGAUUACCAGCAUAUUCCUACAGUGCUGUAUGCCUUUUAGUUCUCCAGGGAAUAGGAAAGACAAGAUACAUGCUUGUUCUCUCCUUUUACUGGCAGUUUUUAAAAACAGACUGUUUCUUAGAGCAUUUUCAGGUUCACAGCAAAAUUGAAGAAGUACGAAGAGUUCCCAUAUCCCCCCAAUCCACAUGUACAUAGCCUGCCCCACUCUCAACAUCCCCCACUAGAGUGGCACAUUGUUUCCAAUUGAUGAACCUAUGUUGACAUGUCCUUAUUACGCAAAGUCUUUAGGCUUCAUUAGGGUUCACUCUUGGUGUUGUACAUUAUAUGGGUUAUAUUAUAUAUUAAAUGCAGAGUGAUGUCUAUUCACCAUUAUGGUAUCAUAGAGAAUAGUUUCACUGCCCUAUAAAUCCUCUGUGCUUUCUGCCUAUUUAUCGCUCCCUCCUCUCAACCCCUGGCACUGAUCUUUUUACUGUCUUCAUAGUUUUGCUGUUUCCAGAAAUGUCAUAUAGUUGGAAUUGUAACAAUUUUAAAAAUAAUGAAUUUGGUUCCCUAUCUUCUCUGAAGGUGAUUUUCUUUCCUUUUUGUUUUUUGAAUUGUUAUGAACUCAUUUGUUGGGGUUCAGUCCAUUGUAAUUCUUACACCUGUUAAAGCUCAAAUUGUUCGUUUUUGGCCAAGGGCAGCCUCUUCUGGUAGGCUUCUGAGUCCUUCUAAAGUGACUCAUAGUCUGUGAUUUGUCCCCUCACUACCUUAUAAAAUGAGACUUUCCGGGAACAUCUUUUACAAUUUCUGCCUCACACCUGGAAUAUCUCCAAGAAGCCUUGGGUUUUUUUCAGUGGGAAAUGGUAUUUCAAAACCACUGCCAGGACUGUUGGGGUGUUCUAAUGCUUAUUGCUACUGAGUUAGUCUUCGUUUCUAAUUCUAAGUGGAUAGUGCUGGGAGGUACUACCCUCGGAAUCCUGGUUUUCAAGGACAUAGGUGUGGUAGAAUAUUUGAUAAUUACUCGUUUAUUUUGUCACAUAUUAUGUCUCUGACAGUUACAAAACAACAAUACUAAUAUAUCCACCAUGGGUUGAAACCAGUUAAAACCAUUCUUUGCAUGCGCUCUCCAUUUCCCCCCAUUCCCUGUGCAGUUGUCUUCCAUAUAUCACCAGGGCAUGUUGCCAUUAGAACGCACACCCAUUAUGCGCCCUUGUAUUCUGUUCCUCUUCGUCCCUGUGUAGUCGACAGGUAACUAUUUAGCGCUCACCUCUAUUCCUAUGUCAGUAUCCCUCUAUCUACAUGGGUUCUCUCAAACUCAUUUUCUAGUAGAUAUCUCUAGAAGGGCUUAUGGGAACAAUAUUCCCUGAGUUUUUGUAUGUUGAUAAUAUGUAUAAUGUUUAUACUCGAAAGUUCUACUGGCCAUAAAAUUCUUGGCUUUCAUUUUCCUUCCUUGAGUAUUUUAUUUUCUGGUAUAAUAUGUUGCUUUGGAAAGUUUGUUGUUAAUGUAGUUUUUUUCCCUUAUAAAUUACUUGAUGUUUUUGCCUAGAUGCUCAAGUUUAUUUUUUCCUUAAAAAUCCUGCAAUUUUACUAUAUCUUGGUAUUGAUUAUUUUGGCCCAGUAUUUUCCAGUAUGCAAUGUGUGCCUUAAAUAUGUAGUUUCUAAUUUUUUUCUGGUGUCCUGGCAUGUCAUCCAGGCUGGCCUCUAAUUCCUGGGCUCAAGUGAUCCUCUCGCCUCAGCUUCCCCAAUGCUGAGAGUAUGGGCUGCAUUAGCUCUUUUUUCUUAAUUUUGGCAAAAAUUUCUUGGAUUACAGUUUUUAGUGUUGCUUGUUCUCCUGCUUUUGCUUUCUCCAGGGAUUCCUGUUAUAUAAGAAAUAGGAACAAUUUUUGUUGCUUUCUUUAGAAUCCUAUUAUUUCAUCAUUUCGUUUUUGGUUUUUAGAAUUAUCUUCCUUCUUACUUUCAAUUUCUCGAAGGCAUUAUCUGUAAUAUUCAUUCUUGUGUUCCUUGGGUUUUAUUCUUCAUUUCUCAAAUAAAUUUUUAAAUUUCUAAUUACUUACUGAGUCAUGUUCUCACAUUUCUGAGUUUCUUCUGUUCUGAUGUUGUUUUUCAUGCUUUAUAUAAUUUUCUUAAUGUUUUUAGCUCAUUUUGAAAUACUAAUAGUAGGUUCUAAUUUUAAUCUCCUUUGUGUUUCUGGCCUUCUAGCAUGAUGUAUUUGUCUGUAAGGAGGAUGUUGUUUUGUUGUUUUGUUCCCGAUUCCUUCACUGUUUUUUUUUGUUUGUUUGUUUUUUUGAGACGGAGUCUUACUCUGUCGCCUGGGCUGGAGCGCAGUGGUGCUAUCUCGGCUCUCUACAACCUCUGCCUCCUGAGUUCAGGCAAUUCUUCUGCCUCAGCCUCCCGAGUAGCUGGGACUAUAGGUGCGCGCCACCAUGCUCGGCUAAUUUUUGUAUUUUUAGUAGAGACAGGGUUUCACCAUAUUGGCCAGGCUUGUCUUGAACUCCUGACCUCGUGGUCUGCCGCCUCGGCCUCCCAAAGUACUGGGAUUACAGGCGUGAGCUACCAUGCCUAGCCCCUUCCCCAUUUUCUUAUAAUAACUUCUAUGAGAUUUGGAUCUGAAAACUUUGCCAUGGGUCAGUUUUAUUGGAAGUUCAUUUUCCUGAAUGUUUGGAAGAAAGCCUAGUGACUCAGGAUAGCAUUUCUAAUUUCACAGAGUUAUUUUUCCGUUAUGAAACACAGAUUGCCUUUGAGGUCUCCUGUUUCUACUACUGCCCCUCACUUUUAUGUGGGCCUCCUCUUUCCUUUGUUUCUGGAGAACCUUUUCCUGUUCAAUUCUGUUUUAAUUUUCAGCAGUUUUUUUUCUGUGUGAGUGAGGCUGUUUCCUAGCAGGGAGGUCUGGUUGGUCAUUUUCAAGUUCAUCAGGGCUUCAUCAGGGCUUGUCCACUUCAACCCUUACGCUAUAGGCCCUUUGCACCAUCUGCAUCUUCAAAUGUGCCCACUGUUCGUUCCAAUGAAGACUUGUUUGUUAUUUGGCUUGUAGAGGGACAUGGAAGAAGCAAAUCAGUCUUUACCUCUCUCAAGGCUGGAGAUUUGCAGGCACUGGUUUUAUCUGUAACUGGAGAUGAGAGUUCAGGCCAAACACUGGUUUAAAAAUCUGUAUAUGAAAUAGCGAUACCCUGGAAUCUAGGACUGAGAUCCUGUGCCUCACACCCACCCACGCGGCCAAGUGCCUACCUGUGGCAGUGACUUCUUAGUGCUCGUCCACAUCUAGGUCUUCUUUAGUCCCAGGCUGAUGGGAACAUUUAAUUCCUUUGCUCCUUGAUGUUAGAUGGGAUCAGGUGACUGAUGCUGGCCAGUGGACUUUGAGGGAGGUUGUGUUACUUCUGAGUUGGCAUAGUGAAAAGCCCAUGAAGAUGCUCUGCUCUCUUUCUUGCCUAGGAUAUCCCUGGUCAUAGGAUUCAUUUGAUGCAGGAACAAGGUGGUCAGCCUGGCUCUUUGAAUAACUGGAAAUGGCCCCUGCAUACCCGUGUUGGACAUAUUACAUGAGGCAGAAAUAAAUUUCUGUUGUGCUAAGCCAUUGAAAUGUUGGGGUUGUUACCACAGCAUCACUUAGACCUGUGCUGUCUAACAUGGCAGCCACUAGGCUACAUGUGGCCAUGAGCACUUGAAAUGUGGCUAGUCCUAAUUAAGAUGUGCUGUAACUUUAAAAUAAUACUAUAUUUGGAAAAAAAGGUGUAAAAUAUCUUAAUAAUUUUUAUAUUACAUAUUAACAUCUUGUAUUCAUUGGGUUAAAUAAGAUGUAUUGAAAUUAUUUUCAGCUUUCUCUUUAGUUUUUUUCAUGAAGCUGCUUAGAAAAUUUAAAAUUAUACACGUGGUCACAUUUGUGGCAUUAUCCGCAGCACUGACCCCUACCUUAGUAAUUCAGUACCCCUCCCUCAUUUUGACAAAAGCUGGUCAGUUGAUUGUCAGAGAAACUGAAUCAGUGAAACUCCAGAUUUGAAGAGAGUACAGAAGAGGAGUACACUACAGAUGGGGAUUAAGCGAAAGUCGACCUACUGGAUCAGGAGAUACACUUCCUUGUCUUUAAUUUCUGUCCAUGUCCUUUUUCCACUUGUUUGCAGAGCACUGACAAUUGGAGUUAUACACUUCACCUAGGAGACUGAAGGACUCUUUUCUAAGAAAUCGAAUGGCUUCAGGAAAGAGAUCAACAGAGCCCGAUAUUUAAGGCUCUCCGUAUCUGCACAAGCAGGAGUUACCCUGCAGUAAAGCCUGCUAGUUCACAAGCCUCACCUACAUGCAGAGAGGGUCCAGUUGGGGUUGACGAACCACUCUUUAUGGGAACAGCACCCAAGAUACACCAGACACUGGUGGAAAAUUCUAACAGGAAUUAACUUGUUAAGGGAAAGAUAAUAAUAAUAUGAGUCUAUGUGCAUAUUAUCAGUGAUCUGUUUGCAUAUUAAAUAAUUCAGAUAAUGAAAGUACAAGUGAAAAAAUGAGUCUUUGCGAUAAAGCUCUUCUCCAGCCAUCCCCAUUUCUACAAUAUUUUUUUCCAAUUUUUAAAAUCAAGGUAAAAUAUACAUACCCCAAAUUUAUCAUUUUAACCAUUUUUAAGUAUAUAGUUCAGUGGUAUUAAAUACAUUCAUAAUGUUGUGCAACCAUCACCACCAUCCAUCUCCCAUACUCUUUUCAUCUGGUGAAGCUGAAAAUAUACUCAUCUUGUAAAGCUGAAAUAACAACUCUCCCUUCUUCCCUUUCCCCAUCCUUGGCAACCAUGAUUCUACUGAUGUCUCUAUGAUCUUGACUACUAAGUACGUCAUAUAAGUGGCAUCAUUUAGUAUUUUUCUUUUUGGUGGCUGGCUUAUUUCACUUAGCAUAAUGUCUUCAAGGUUUAUGUUGUGGCAUGUCUCAGAAUUUCCCUCCUCCUUAAGGCUGAACAAUACUCCAUUGUAUGCAUAUACCACAUUUUGCUUAUCCAUUCAUUCAUCCAUGGAUACUUGGGUUACUUUCACAUUUUAGCUGUUGUGAAUAAUGCUGCCAUUAACGUGGAUAUGCAACUAAAAGAGUACUGUAAACAAAUGCCAACAAAUUGGAUAACCUGGAUGAAAUGGACAGAUUCCUAGAAACACAAAACCUACUAAGACUAAAUAAUGAAGAAACAGAAUAUCAGAAUAGACCUGUAACUAGUGAGGAGAUUGAAUGAGUAAUCAAAAAUCUCCUGACAGAAAAGAAAAACCCUGGACCUGAUGGCUUCACUGGUGAAUUCUACCAAACAUUUAAGGAAAAACUAAUACCAUUCUUCAAGUUUUCAAAAACAAAAAAAACUGGAGAAAGAGAACCCUUUCCAACUCAUUCUAUGAGGCCAACAUCACACUGACACCAAAGUUAGACAAAGAUACUACAAGGAAACUACAGAUAAUACUUCUUAGGAACGUUGAUGCCAAAAUCUUCAAUAAAGUACUAGCAGAGUUUCCUCUAAUAUUUUAAGAAGUUUGCUGAAGUGUGAAUAGUUCUUUGAUUAAUAUUUUUUCGAGACGGAGUCUCACCGUGUUGCCCAGGCUGGAGUGUAAUGGCAUGAUCUCAGCUCACUGCAACCUCUGCUUCCCGGGUUCAAACGAUUCUCCUGCCUCAGCCUCCUAAGUAGCUAGGAUUACAGGCACCUGCCACCAUGCCUGGCUAAUUUUUGUACUUUUAGUAGAGACAGGGUUUCCCCAUGUUGGCCAAGCUGGUCUCGAACUCCUGACCUCGUGAUCUGCCCUCCUCGGCCUCCAAAAGUGCUGGGAUUACAGGUGUGAGCCACCGUGUCCCGCCAGCUAAUAAUUUUAGGGAGCAGAUGAAGAGGUCUUCAGACUGCUUUUAGCUCAGGUUUUUUUGUUUUAAAAUUUAUUAAGUGGAAAGAAACAUGUUAACUGAAGAUUGAAGUUUGCUGAAGUAUGAAUAGUUCUUCGGUUAAUAAUUUUAGGGCGCAGAUGAAGAGGCUUUCAGAUUGCUUUUGUCUCAGGAUUUUUUGCUUUAAAAUUUAUAAAGUGAAUGGAAAGAAACGUUAACUGAGGAUUAGUGCUAGUUUUUCUUGACAGGUCAUUUCCUAUAGGGAGGGCAGUAGUAUAAGCAAAACAACAAAAUAUUCAAAAUUCUCAAAUAAGUACUAUUUAUUAUUGAAAAACUCAGAUAAAUGUAGAAGUUAUUUUUUCUCUCUAUUGAGCAGCAGUUACAUAUGCUAGAAUCAUAGUUUGAAUGAUUCAGACUGUGUACCUGUGAUCUGACAUACCUGGAUUGGAGUUCCAUCUCUGCCACCCACUUUAUUUGACUCCAUAGAGAAAUUACUCAAGCCCCUUAAGACAGACACUGAAAUAGGAUACAGUUUCCAAGAAGGCAAGAUUUUUUGGAUUUUUUUGUUGUUGUUCAUUGCUGUAUGCUGAGGUUUAGAUUAGUUCCUGGGACACAGAACUAGCAGUCAGUAAAUACGUUGAAUGAACCCGAAGAAUUCCUGCCUCCGAAUUGUUUUGGGGAUGAAAUGCGGUAAUGCAUGUAAAGCAUUGGGCAUGCAAGUGAAGCCAGCCACGUAUUAAACAGUACUCAGCUCUUACCUCUGUAUCUUAUAUUCUUAUUUCCGUGACUGUAUCCUCACACAUGAAGAAAUGGCUACUUAUUUAUUAUUAUUAUUACUAUUAUUAUUGCUACUUAUUUUUUAAAGCCACUUACAUCUCUGGAGAUCUCUGUAUGUGUGUUAAAAAUACCAUGUUUUGUAACAAUUGGCUUGUCUUAGAAAACUUUUCAAUUAUACAGAAUUUGAGAUCUUUACAACUUGAAUUUUCUUUUUUUUCUUUUUGAGUCUCGCUCUGUCUCCCAGGCUGGAGUGCAGUGGUGCGAUCUCAGGUCACUGCAGUCUCUGCCUCCUGGGCUCAAGCGAUUCUCCUGCCUCAGCCUCCUGAGUACAGGCACGCGCCACCAUGCCCAACUAAUUUUUGUAUUUUUAGUAGAGAUGGGGUUUCAUCAUUUUGGCCAGGAUGGUCUCGAUCUCCUGACCUCGUGAUCCGCCCACUUCGGCCUCCCCAAGUGCUAGGAUUACAGGCGUGAGCCACCGUGCCCGGCCACAACUUGAAUUUUCAUAGCAAACUAGUUUUUAUUGUCAAAUUAGAAAUUUAUGCUUGAAGCCUAGUGCUUCUUUUGCCUAUGCAUCUCAUCUAAAAGUAAUGGCACUUAUCACGUCAGCCUCAUGGAUUGUGGUAGUGGUUGUUAUCCUUGGAAUUACCGGUAGGGUAACAGUCUCCAGGCAUACCAUGGGUUCUUCAGUUAUGAGUGGCAUAGCUUAUGUACAUGUUAACUGUGAAUAAUAAACGAUUUUUCCAACUUACUGCAAUACUCUUAUUUAUGUCUGUAAUGUGAAUUGUCCAGAGGAGAAGUUGUGGUCAAUUGAUGAUUAGGCUGAUGGUUUCUGCUAGCUCUGGCAAAAGGUGAAUCCAGUUGCUUUCUAGCACUUUUCCUACUAACCCUGCUUCUCACCCUGUACCUAAUACCACAUUUUUAGUUUAGUUUUUGUUUUGUUUUGUUUGAGACAGGGUCUAACUUUCUGACACCCAGACUGGAGUGCAGUGGUGUGAUCAUAGCUCGUCUGCAGCCUCCACCUCCCAGGCUCAAGUGGUUCUCUCACCUCAGCCUCCUGAAUAGCUGGGACUACAGGAUUAUGCCCCCAUGCCUGGCUGUUUAAAAAUUUUUGGGUAGAGAUGGGGUUUUGCCACGUUGCCAUGGCUGGUCUCAAACUACUGGGUUUAAGCAAUCCUCUUGCCUUGGCCUCCCAAAGUGUUGGGAUUACAGGCAUGAGCCACUGCACCCAGAAUCACCUUUUUUUAGUUUGGAAGAUGACAUCUUUUUUUUUUUUUUUCUUAGAGAAGCUAGAGGGUACCAAAUUAAAGUCUGUCAGUUUUUUCUGUCUCCACCUCAAAGAUCACUGUAUGACUUCUUUUCUUCCUUCUCGGCUGUUUCACACGAAGUUUUCCCUUUUUCUAAGGCUCAGUCCUUAUCGUCUGAGACCUCCCUCUCAUUAUCCAUCUCUCCAUCCUUGACUGUUUCUAGUUCGAUUGUAACACUGAUCAAAUCUCCUUCAAGUUCAAAACAAACCAGCAAAACCUUCCCUUGAUACUGCCAUUACCUCAGAGCUAUGUACCGUGCUCCUUGCCCUCCCCCCGGACUUCUCCGGAUGCUAGUUGAUGCCUGUUUAGCACCUGUCACUGUUUCAUAUACUUCUUACUGGCCACUGCCUGGUUGGCAUCUACCACUUCUCUGGAAUCAGCAACCCCAAUAGCAGAUUUAACUGCUGGUUCCAUGGUUUUUGUUACUUGUCCUUUUUUGCAGUGUUUUAAAUAAUAAUCAUCUUUUCACUUAUUUUUUUAAAGAAGGUCAUUUAAAAAAAUCAUCCUGCAGUGGAAAAUUUGGAAAAUAUGGAAAAGUAUAAAGAAGACAAUUAUCAACUGUAAUACCAGCAGUACCUAUUGUUAAGCUCUAGGGCAUGUCAUUUCCAUCGCUCUCUUUUUAAAUGCAUUAAACAGAAAAGGAUCACAUGGUUAUUUUGUGAUCUGAUUUUUUCUAUCUUAAUAUAUUGUGAGUAUAUUUCCAAGUACUUAUUCUCGUGUGGCAUAACAUUUGUAGUUACACGAAGUGGCGGUGUUGAGACUGCCUUGGUUCAAAUCCUGGCUUCAGUUACUGCUGCAGUGUGACCUGAAGGAAGUUACUCCUCUGGGUUUUAGUUUCCUCAUCUUGAAAAUAGUUAUAACAUUCUUACUAACUUCUAGGGUUGCUGUAAGUAUUAAGUGAGCUAACACAUAGAAAUAAUUCUUGGCACUUAAUAAACAUCAGCUGUUAUUAACAAUAUUGUCUGACUGUACUAUAAUUUACAUUAUUUUUGUUUUUGCUUGUUCUGCCGUCAUUAAGCGUGUUGUAAGACCAUACGUGUCACUAAAUCUGGGUGCACAACAUGAUUUUUUUUAAAUGUGGAUUUUUAUUAGUAGGAUUGCUCAGCUAGUGGGUACAUCAUGCUCAUUGCUAAGUUGCUCUCUAGAGAGGCUGCAUUUAUACCUCCCAAGGCUGUACAGGAGACCAUUAACUUCAUUACAUUUUUCCAAAAAACUUUAUGCUAUUGCCCACAUUUUGUGCUGCUCCCUUGCUAAAAGUGAAUAACAAUAUGAUCAUGUUGUUACCUCUCUCUUGCCAAAACGUUGACUUGAUGAUAAGGGGAUCACUGUGACAUCAUCAUUACCCACAGAUGUUUCUUUUUUCUCCCCCCUCCCCCUCUCUUCUCCUUCCUCCCUCCUUUUGUUUCUUGAGACGGGUUCUUGGCUCUGUGCAGGCUGGAGUGCAGUGACACAAUCAUGGCUCACUGCAGUCUGGACCUCCCAGGCUCAAGUGGUCCUCUCACUUCAGCCUCCUGAGUAGCUGGGACAGCAGGCACGCACCACCACACCCAGCUAAUUUUUGUAUUUUUUGUAGAGAGGGGUUUUACCACGUUCCUAGGCUGGUCUCGAACUGCAUGUUCCCAGGCUGGUCUCGAACUCGUGGGCUCAAGCGAUCCACCCACCUCGGCCUCCCAAAUUGCUGGGAUUACAGACCCGAGCCAGCAUGCCUGGCCUCACAGAUAUUUCUUGAUCUACAUUUUAUUCAUUAUUUAGGUCCAACUUUAGCAUGUGUCAUGUAUUUAUAUACAGGUUCUAAAUCUUUCCAUUUGAAAAAUACUCAUUUUUCUAUCCAAAAUGAAUUCAAUUUUCCUUUUUAUUCUAGUCCCAGUCUGUGUAUGAGUAAAACCCCAAGGACCCUGUAUCCUGAUUUUACUAUUUUUUGUUAAUGGUUUGAAACAGCUUUAUUAAGAUAUAAUUCACAUACCAUACAAUUAUUUAAAGGGCACACACUUCAAUGGUUUUUAGUAUACUCACGGAUCUGUACAACCAUUAUCACAGUCAUGGGCAAUUGGUUCAGGAUUUGGGAAGAAAACGUAUGGCAUUAGGAUUAAAAGUACAAUGUUUAGAGUCUGGCUGAUCUGGGUUUAAAUCCCAAAUCUACCAUGUAUUAACUGUGUGACUUUGAGAAGGUUACUUAAUCACUAUGAGCUUCAGUUUUCUUUUUUUUUCCCGUUUUUAUUUUUAUUUUUAUUUUUAUUUUGAGGCAGAGUCUUACUCUGUCACCCAGGCUGGAGUGCAGUGGCGCGAUCUCGGCUCACUGCAACCUCUGCCUCCUGGGUUCAAGUGAUUCUUUGCCUCAGCCUCCCAAGUAGCUGGGAUUACAGGCCACCAUGCUUGGCUAAUUUUUGUAUUUUUAGUAGAGAUGGAGUUUCACCAUGUUGGCCAGGCUGGUCUCGAACUCCUGACCUCAGGUGAUAUGCCCGCCUCAGCCUCCCAGAGUGCUGGGAUUAUAGAUGCAAGCCACUGUGCCGGCCUGAGCUUCAGUUUUCUUAUCUGUAAUAUGGGAUUACUAGUGGUAUCUGGCUCAUAGGCUUAUUUUAAGGAUUAAGCAAGAUAAUAAAUGUAUAGAAUUUAGCACAGUAACCGGCACAUAGUAAAUGUUUGAUAAAUGGAACUCGGUAAAUAUUAUUGCCAUAAUUUUGUUCUUAAAUCAACCAGCAAGUGUUUGAUGCUAUUAUUAGGCAAUGUUAUUAAAUAAUGGAAGGUGUUUCUACCAGUGAUUCACAGUGUUUUCUGUAUCCAGCAAGCUUUUAAUACAGCUGCUUGUAUUAUUCUCCCGUAUAAACUUCUAAUUACUCUCUGAAAAUACAGUUGGUUUCCUGUUGAUAGAGAACAAUAACAGUAGCUUACACUUAGUGCUUACUGUCUGCCUGGCACUGUUCUAAGUGCCAUACCUAUAUUAACUCCUUUGAUCCUCAUUUUACAGAUUGGGUACGGAGGAGGUUAAACAACUUGGUCAAAGGAUUACAACAGUUAAGUGGUGGAGCCAGGAUUCUAACCUUGGUAUUCAGUCUGGCUACAGAGCCCAUGCUCUUUCUUAUCUUUAUGUUCUUCUCUUUACUUCCUAAAGAAUGGUAGAUGCAUUUCAAACAUCCUGACAUCUUGGCUGCUGAGGAUUCUGUAUGGAAAAGCACUAUGAGGUCUUUAAUGCUUGGUUGGAAGGAGAACUAAAAUGAGCAGUUGUGUGUGCUGUGGGCAUGGGCCUUAGGGCAGCUGUAUAUUUGUCAUCUGGAUCAGACCAUACAUUGGUGAUCCUGCUUCACAACCAUAGAAUCCAGACCCUCCAUGGGGCCAUGACCAGCCACAAAGUAUCCUCCCUGACCCUCCCUGUGGAAUGCUCGUGUGAACUUGCACUACUCCCUCCUUGCAUAGUAUCAAAUCCUGCGGAUCCUUGGAAGGCCACCUUAAAUUACUUCCCACCUGUGAAGCAGUAAACGUUAGUGCUCUUCGGUUAAUCAUCAUGUGUGGUGGUAUGACAUUUGCAGUAUCAUCUGUUACCAUUAUUUAAAUUUGAAUAUCUUUAUGUCUUGGCUCCUCAUGUUGAUUACAUGUUUCUUGCAGGCAGGGAACUAUGUCUUAAAUGUUUUAAAAUUUGCUUUAAUGGCCCCUGGAAAUAUUACCAAGGGUUGUGUGUGUGUGUGUGUGUGUGUGUGUGUGUUUCUUUCAGUCUCACUUGUCUGUCGAUAAUAGAAUAUCUCUGAAAUUCAAACAUACCUAGCCUCACAAACUUAGUCCCAAAGGUACAUGCUGUGUUUUUGCAAGAAGGUGGGCAGUCCCUAGUUGGCUGUUGGAUUAUGUGCAUUGUGUUGGGGUAGUAGUUGCUGCUAAUUGCCUGUCUGCAGCUCCUCAGAACCUGUUGUUGCUUCCUUUUGAAACCUUCCUUGAUUGCCCUAGUUGCUGCUCAUCCUGCAUCCAGGCCCCUCCCUUAGGCAUGUGACUCACGGAUUUAAAAGACAGUGCUGUACGGUAAUUAACUACCUGCCUCUCAUCACACAGAGAUGAGAACUUAAAUGUAGGCUUCCCAUCUAAAACUUUCUUCCCUGUGUGUUUAUCCACCCACGGACAUGGAGCAGCGCUGUCCCACACCUGGCCUUUUGGAGGAAAUAUUGCUAGACUUAUUUCUCCUGUUUGAAAUCACUAGUUGGCAUAUUCGUGUACAAGGGAUGGAUUUUACAUGGGUGCUCUUAAUUGAAAAUAAUUUUAUUUUCUGUAACUUCUAGAAUUUUGUUAGUUUAUUGAUGCACACAUAUUGGGUGGGUGACAGUUGGGUUUUUUAUGAAGAUAAUUUUAAGUUUUUAGUAAAUAAUUAAGUCAAGUAUUACAUGACAGUUUAAUUGGACUAAAUUCUGACAUAACCUAUACAUCCUUAAGGUGACCGGUGGUUAUCAUUUUCUAUGAAAUGUAAUUAGUUUUUCAGGAAACUUUGUCCACAUAAAGGAAUUGAUUCCACCCUUACUACCUGCUUAGCAAUCCUGAAAAAUAUUGUAAAUAUAAUCUUAGAGUAUGCAUCAUUAGGAAAUAAAUCUAUUUUGAGAAAUAAAUUUUAACGUACACUAUUAAUAGGACAUUUAGAAAUGUAAUUUUCUAAAUAUAUUAGAAAUAAUAGGACAUUUAGAAAUGACAUUCUUUUUUUUUUUUUCCUUGCUUUUUGUUUGUUUGUUUGUUUUAAGACAGGGACUCACUCUGUUUCCUAGGCUGGAGUGCAAUGGCGUGAUCAUUGCUCACUGCAGCCUCAACCUCCUGGGCUCAAGCGAUCCUCCCACCUCAGCCUCUGAAAGUGCUAGGAUUACAGGGUUAGCCACCAGCACCCAGCCAAGAAAUCCCAUUCUAAUGUAUUAGUAUGGUUUUAUCUAUUUUAGCAGUGUAAAAUAAAGUCUUUGUGAAUUAUAUAUAGUAUAAUUGAAUUGCCAAAAUAAACAUCCUUGCCCUCAAAUUGCUUAUGAUAUUGUUUCUGAAGCACAGACAUAAUCUUUUGACCUUUUAAGCAAAAAAUUAAUUUUUCAUUUAACUUUUUUUGUUUGUGUGUGUGUGUGUGUGUGUGUGACAGGGUCUUGCCCUGUUGCCCAGGCUAGAGUAUAGUGAUGCAAUGAUGGUUUACUGCAGCCUCAACUUCCCAGGCUCAAGUGAUCCUCCCACCUCAGCCUCCUGAGUAAUUGGGACUGCAGGCACGUGCCACCAUACUUGGCUAAAUUAACAUUUUUUUGUGGAAAUAUGGUCUUGCUAUGUUGCCCACACUGGUCUUGAACUCACGGGCUGAAGUGAUCCUCCUGCUUCAGUCACCCAAAGUACUGGGAUUACAGGUGUGAGCCAUCGUGCCUGGCCUUUCAUUCAACUUGUAAUUCACAAUUUCCAGAAAAAAAGUUUUAAAAUUACUGAUGGAGGAAAGAUCUUUGGGACUUGCUUGUAAAUAUGUUAAUAUUUGAUCUUAAUAAGCUCUGUCAUACUAACACUGUUUAUUAAACUUUGUGGUAGAAUUACUACCCAUAACUAAAGAAUGAAAUGCAUAUAUUUGCAAAUUGUUAAAAAUUUAUAAAUCGAUAGAAAAGUUGAAUGAAUAGUGAACACCCUUGUGUCUUUCACUAACUCAGUGGCUCACUUGCUAACGUUUGCCUCAUUUGCUUUCUCUGUUUAUAAAGACAUAUAUACUUUUUUUAUUCCCCUGAGCCAUUUGAAAGUAAGCUGCAAACAUCUUGACAUUUAACUUCUAAACAUUUUAGCACGUGUAUCCUAAGAGCAAGGUUGUCUUCCUGAAGAGUUACAUUAUCAUACUUAAGAGAUAUAGUAUUAAUACAAUAUUAUCUAACAUGUGAUCCCUAUUUAAAUUUCAUUUAUUUUCUUCCCCAGAACAGUUCUUUAUAGAUGUUUUAAUUUUUGAUCCAGAAACCAAGGGAAAAAAUAUAUCUAUAUCUAUAGAGAGCUAAAUAGAUCUAUAUUUGAUCCAGAAACCAAUCAAGGAAACACACACACACACACACACACACACACACCCGCUUUUGGCUGUCAUAUUUCUUUAGUUUCCUUUACUUUAGGAUAAGCCACUACCCCACCUCCAUCUACCACCCGGCAGUGGUCUUUUAUGAAAUCUCAUCAUAUUUUUCCUUUUCUUAUAUAAGCAGUCCCACAAUUUGCUGGUUAUAUUUCAUGCCUAGAUUAAAAUAAGAAUAUUUUGGAAUGAAUAUACUAUAUAGAUGGCAUUAAUUUUCCAUUAUAUUACAUUAGGAGAAGUAAUUUUUUUUACAUGUUUUUUUUCCGCUGUAUAAUAGUUUAGUAUUUGUUUUAAUAUACUUCUGUUAAAGAUUUGUGAUACUGUGUCUUUAAAUUUCAAAAUAGAAUUUUGUAAUUUACUCUUAAUUUUCUUAGUAUGUUGUAUUCCAAAAUUAUAGAAAGUGCUAUAAUAGACAUUUAUGUACAUUACAUAAAGUAAUAGACAUUUAUGUAAUGUGGGCAUAGAUUUAAAUUUUUUUUAAAUUGUUAAAAUAUUAACAUUUAACCAUGUCUGCUUUAGAUAGGUUUAAUCUUACAAGGAUCUAUCUACUUAUCUUUCUAUCUAUUUAUAAUGUAUAUAUCCAUUUUAAAUAAUAAUAACAAUACAUGAAUAAAUCUGGUCCAAACUUCUAUCUUGAGAAAUGUAACAGCAAUUUUGAACUCCUUCAUCCCUCAAGACAAUUAUUCCUCCCUUCCCAGAGGUAACCAUCCUCCUAAAUUUGAUGUCAUUCCCUUAGUUUUUUCUUAAGUUUUACCACAUUUGUGUUGUCCCUUUAACAUACUUUUUUUUUUAAGCUUUUCCUGUUUUUGAGCUUUAUACAUAUGGAAUUAUUCUGUAUAUAUUCUUCUUGGGCUUGAUUUUUUUAUUUAUAUUACAAUUUUGAGAUGUCAUUUAUGUUGACAUUGUUAGCCGAAGUUCAUUAAUUUUUCACUAUUUGAUAUAAUAUUCCAAAUUACUGGAAUAUGGAAUAUUCUAUGAAUAUACCACAGUCCAUUUUACUGCUGCUUGACACCUCGGUUUCACCUAGUUUUUGGUAUGGAAAAAAUACUGCUUUAAAUAUUCUUUUGCGUGGCUCAUGGUAGCUAAGUACAAAAGGUUCUCUAGGUUAUAUGCAUAGACCUGGAUUGUUGAGUCUUGGGUGUAUACACCAUCAGCUUUACUAGGUAUGGCAGAAUGUCUUCUUUUACACAGUUGUGGAAUAAGCCAGAUGAGUUCAAGAGGAGCAAGUUUGUGAGAGGAUGGACAAGUGAGUUAGUGAGUUACAUUUCAUUUGUUUUGAGUUUUAGCCUAUUUAGUUAGAAAUGUUAAGUAGGCAUUUGAGAUGUGUUUACUUUUUUAGCUCCACCCAUCUUUGUUUUUUCCUAGGUUGACUCAUUCAGGUAUGUCAUCUCUCCCUUCUCCUUAAAGUGGCCUUUAAAGAAAAAAGUUGCAGGCCGGGCACGGUGGUUUACACCUAUAAUCCCAGCACUUUGGGAGGCCAAAGAGGGCGGAUCACAAGAUCAGGAGUUCAAGACCAGCUUGGCCAAUAUGGUGAAACCGCAUUUCUACUAAAAAUAAAAAAAUUAGCCGAGCGUGGUGACACGUGCCUGUAAUCCCAGCCACUUGGGAGGCUGAGGCAGGAGAAUCACUGGACCUAGGGAGGUGGAGGUUGCAGUGAGCCGAAAUCGUGCCACUGCACUCUACCCUGGGUGACAGAGUGAGACUCUGUCUCAAGGAAAAAAUUGCAGUAUCAUGGUACAACAAUUACUUGAUCGUAAUAGAAGAUGUGUUCAGUUUUUAUAUCUUCAGUCUCAGGCCAUCCGUCAUAUGCAGCCUUUUUGUUUUUAUAGACCUUGAACCACAGAACUACAUUAAGCUAGUUUGCUGUUUUCCAGGGAUGACAUAAAGGAGAAGUGGGUAGAGGGUGAUGCUGUUAUUAGCAAGUGUGCAUUCCAGGUAGCGGUUCACAAAGGGGAAAAAACGUAAAGGAAAGACGGGUGCAAGCUAAAACAAAUAAGCCAGUAAGUAAAAAACCACAACACUCUUUUGUGAUUAUUUAGAUCUGAAACAAAUAGCAGCAUGUAUUAAUAGUCCCUGAUGAUUUCACUGUAUUGUAGCAUAACUCUGGUAUUCAUAAUGUCAAUUCUGAAUUUCUUUAUGUGUUGAGAGAGUGUAAUCAUGCUGAUUUUAGCAGAUCUGGUGAACCCUUAGCAAUCUAGAAUCACUCUCUGAUAAUUCCUGAAUUAACAGUAGAAAUUUAACUGUUUUAUGUGGUGAAAUUAUUCUAGGAAGCUUGUUCCAUGGGACAUUUACCUAUUAGCUAAUAAAACAAAUGGUCUAUUGAUAAUUUCUCAAAAGCUCUGUAUAAAAAAAAAAUAUAUAUACAAUAAUUUCUCUACUGGCCGAAUUGGAUUUACUUGGAAAAAGAAAGAGGGUGUUAUCAAAAAAUUUAAAUGUCUUGUUAGGUUCGUAAGUUGUAGAACAAGAAUGAGAAUGUGCAAGUGUUUUUAUGCUUCAUUGUUGGGAAGGAUAAAUUGCAAAAGAACAUAGAGCUGGGUGAUUUUCUGGGGUUCAGUCUGUUGCGGGUGCCACAGAUUGGCACUCCCCUCGGAAUUGCCACACCUUCACGGAGCCAGAACAGGAGGGAUACGGAGGGAAAGGGCCCUUUCCCAACUUCAGACUGAGCACCCAGAAGUUGACCUGGGACUGCUGUUUUGUUUCUAGGAAACUAGAAACCUUGGCAGAAUUGAAAUUUCGUAGUGAUUUUUUCUUCUUUGCUCUCCAAAAAAUAAACUUGUAUGUACACACAUAUGUAUAUACACUCACACCUACAUAAAAGAAAGAUAAUUUCAAAGAAAUAAUAUAUCUCGUAUAGUCCUUGAACAGUUAUUUUACUAUUCAAAGUAGGUUCUUCAAAAUUUUUAAUUUGAAAUAACUAGGUUUACAGGAAAUUGCAAAAAAUAGUAAGGAGAGGUCCCUUGUGCCUUUCACCUUUCCCUUAAUGGUAACUUCUUACUACCCACAGCACAGCAUUAAACUAGAAAUUGACAUUGGUACAUUUUAUGUGUUUAGUGCUGUGCUGUUUAAACAUAUAUGUAGUUGAUUUGUGAACCACUGUGGCAUCAAGACACAAAUGCUGCCACCACCAAGCUCUCCCUUGUGCUGCACACACCUGCCCCAUGGCAGCCAGUAAUCUGCUUUUCAUCUCUAUGAUGUUGACAUUUCGAGGAUAUUAAUAAAUGGAAUCACAUAGUAUGUGACCUUUUAAAAUUAGCUUAUUUUCACUUGGCGCAAUUCCUUGAGAUCUAUCCAAGUUGUGUGAAUCAACAGUUCUUUCCUUUUUAUUGCUGAAUAGGAUUCCAUGGUUUGUUUAACCAUUCACCUUUUGAAAGAUAAUCUCUUUCCCUAGUUUUUGGCUUUUAACAGUAAAGCAGCUGUGAACAUUCAUGUUCAGUUUUUUGUGUGGACAUAAAUUUUUAUUUCUUUGGGAGAGGUGCUGUUAAAGAAAAAAAAAUUAUUCAGUGACACUUGUUAAAGCAUGGGAAGGAAGACAUUAUUCAGGAUCAUCCCUGUAAGUGUAGGGACCACUACAAUAGUGUCUUACAGUGGGUGGGGAGAGAGCGUGGCCUCAGUGCUGGAUGUAGCAUGGGGAAGUGGGAAUUUGUAGCCAAGGAGCUGGUUGAGGGCCAGUGGAUGGAAAAUUCUCAAGAGGAAAUGUCAGGUGUAAGGGGUUUCUGCCUAAACUGACCGUAACAGGAUUCUUUCUUGCUGAAGACAGGCCAAGGUGAUCAGACAUCAGCUGGAGGGUGGCAGAAGAAGAAGAGGGUAAUCAGACACCUUGACGGGAGGUUUGCUAAUCUGGCUUAGCAGGGUUCUUUGCUAAAACAGGAAUUUACAAGGAAGUACACAGAUAGGCCUGGGAGAAAAGUUCAGGAGCCUGGCUCAUUUGGUCAAGCAAAGAAUCUUUGCCAGAGCCCAGGGGUGUGCAGUUGGUGGCUUACCUGUAAGUAGCUGUGCCAUUUUACAUGCUCACUGGCAGUGUAUGAGAGAUCCAGUUUCUUCACAUUCGUGUCCACAUUUGGUGUUGUCACUAUUUUUUUAUUUUAGCUGUGCCAGUAGGUGUGCAGCAUAGUUUGGUUUGCGUUUCCCUGAUGUCUAGUAAUGUUGACCAUAUCUUUUCAUGCGCGUAUUUGCCGUCUAUAUAUCCUCUUCAAUAAAAUGUCUUUAUAUUUCUUGCCCAUUUUCUAGUUGAAAUUUUUUUCAAUUGUUGAGCUUUGAGAUUUCUUUAUAUAUCCUAGAUGAGGCUUUUAUCACAUAUAUUGUUAGCAAAUAUAUUUUCCUAGCCUGUACCUCAUUUUUUUGCCUUCUUAAACAGGUCUUUUGUAGAGCAAACAUUUUUAAUUUUGUUGAAGUUCAGUUUAUCGUGUUUUUUUUUCUUUCAUGGAUUGUAUUUUUGGUGUCAUUCCCCAUUCCCCAUUCCCCACUCUCCAGCCCCAGACGGCCACGAAUCUACUCUCGGUCUCUGUGAAAUUGCCUAUUCUGAAUAUUUCCUAUAAGUGGAAUCAUAUGUCUGGCUUCUUUCACUUAGCAUAUAUUCAGGCCUCAUCCCUGUUGUAUCAUGAACCAGUUCUUUUUAUGGCUUCGUUUAUUUUUAAGGUUGAAUAAUGUUCCACUGCAUGGAUAAGACCACAUUUUGUUUAGCCAUUUGUCAGCUGAUCGGCAAUUAAGGUUGUUUUCACUUCUUCGUCUGCAUCAGUACAGCUGCAUGUGUACCCUUCAGCCCUGCACCUUCCUUAUACACGAUGCACAGAUGUACGCAUGCGAGUACUUGUGUGUACGGUUUUGUUUUCUUUUUUAAAUAAUGGAGGAUUAACUUAUUUUAUAGUUUUUUUCUUCGAUAUUUGGGAUGUCUUUUUAUGUCUAUAUAAAAAGAUAUAUCUCAUUAUUUUAAAUGACUAUGUAGUGUUUAAUGUGACUGCUUAAUUGAUCCUAUUCUAAUAAACAUUUAGAUGACAUUGGGUAACUUCUUGUUUUUCUUUUUUAUAUAACAGUGGCACCAGGCACAGUGGUUUAUGCCUAUAAUCCCAGCACUCUGGGAAGCCAAGGCAGAAGGAUCACUUGAGCCCAGGAAUUUGAGACCUGCCUGGGCAACAUAGAGAGACCUUAUUUCUACAAACGAACAAACAAACAAAAAAUUAUCCAGGCUUGUUGGCACUUGCCUGUAGUCCCAGCUACUUUGGAGGCUGAGGUGGGAGGAUCACUUGAGCCCAGUAGGUGGAGGCUACAGGGAAUUAGGAUUACACCACUGCACUCCAGCUUGGGUGACAGAGCAAGACCCUGUCUCAAAUAAAAAAAUAGUGACACUAAUCAUCCUUGUACAAGUGUCUUUUUUGGUGCAUAGCUCAUUUUACCUACUUUUGGAUUUUUCUCUUCAAUGCCAUUUGUCAUUAACUUAUUUAGAAGUGUAUUGAUUACCUCCUAUAGGCCAGGCACUGUACUGUGUAUCAGACACUAGGGACACAAGCACUAGUAAAAUGCUAUGGCUAUACUCAAGUUUUUUGUAAAGAUGAUAUACCUAUAAGUAGGUAAUCAUGGUUCACUGUGAUAAGUGCACAAUGUGUUAUUACUAGAAUCCUGUGGAACGAACUGUAGCAGAAGGUAAGGCAGGUUACGUUAAAUAGAUUGAAAACAGAUUAUAGCAGUCUGUGAAUGCCCUUCUAAUGAAUUUGGACUUCAUUUUGUACAUAAUUAGAAAUCAUUGAAAAAGGCCGGGCGCGGUGGCUCAUACCUGUAAUCCCAGCACUCUGGGAGGCCUAGGCGGUUGGAUCACGAGGUCAGGAAUUCGAGAUGAGCCUGGCCAAGAUGGUGAAACCCUGUCUCUACUAAAAAUACAAAAGUUAGCUGAGUGUGAUGGCACAUGCCUGUAGUCCCAGCUACUUGGGAGGCUGAGGCAGGAGAAUUGCUUGAACCCGGGAGGCAGAGGUUGUGGUGAGCUGAGUUCGUGCCAUUGCACUCCAGCCUGGGCGACAAGAGCGAAACUCCGUCUAAAAAAAAAAAAAAAAAGAAAUCAUUGAAAAAAUGUAGGCACACUUAAAUUUUUUAACUUUAGUAAAUUUUUGUGCUGUGACUGUUUUAGAACACUUUAUCACCUCCCACAAUCACUGCCUUCUACCUCCUCAUCUAGGCAACCACUGCUUAUUUUCUGUCUCUAAAUUUGCUUUUCCUAAACAUUUAUGCGUUGGAAACAUACAGUAUGCAGUAUUUUUACAUUGGCUUCUUUCAUCUAGCGUGUCUUUGAGGCUCAUGUAUGCUGUAAUGUGUAUCAGUAUUUUGUGCCUUUUUACUGCCUAAUGAUAUUCCAUUCUGUGGUGAUGACAAUUUAUGUGCUCAGCAAUUGAUGGAUGUUUGGAUUGUUUCCAGUUUUUGGUUAUUAUGAACAAAGCUGCUAUGAACAUCUGUAGAUAAAUCUUUGUGUGGGCACAUAUUUCUCUUGGGAAAAGGAAAUUUUGGAUCCUGUGAUAAGUUUAUAUAUAACUUUAAGAAAUUAGGGCAUGGUGGCUCACGCUUAUAAUCCCAGUGACUCGGGAGACUGAGGCGGGAGGAUUGCUUGAGCUCAAGAGGUCAAGGCUGAAGUGAGCCAUGAUUGGGCUACUGCACUCUAGCCUGGACAACAGAGUGAGACCUCACCUCUAAAAGAACAAAGAAAAAAAAUUUACAGACUAUUCCUCAAAGUGACUGCAUCAUUUUACAGUCCUGUCAGCAAUGUAUGCGGGUUCCAGCUUCUCCAGAUGCUCGACACUUGGUAUUGUCUUUUGAUUAUGGCCAUUUUAAUGGCUGUAUAGUGUAUCUCAUUGUAGUUUUAACUUGCAUCUUCCUAAUGACAGGGUGUUUAUAAUCUUUUCAUGAAGCAUAGUUAUAUUUUAGAGACAUGAGUCCAAUGAAUAGAGGUAAGAAUGGAGGUGAGCUACAUGAAAGAUGAGAGCCUACGUCAGACAAUAUGUGUAGAGAUGGGGAGACAUUUUAAAGAUACGUGUAUCAGAGCUAGAAUGAGCAGCAUUUAGUAACUCCUGAGUAUAAUAGAUGAAGCAGAGGGAGGUGGGGCUUGUGAUCCCAAGAUUUUAAACUUCGGCAAUUGGGCACUUUUUGGCUAACGGUGCUGCCAUUAGCCAAAAAGUGACUGCCGGUACAUAAACAGAUUUUGUGCUGGUGGUUGAUGGCUUUUAUAUUGAUCUUAUUCUCUUGAUGUGCCACUGGAAUAAACAUUUAAUAGAGUGUUUGGAAACAUGUAUCUAGUUCAAAAGAAGGAUCUGGGCUGAGGUAUAAAUUUAGGGCAGUUUACAUUGUGUAGGGAACAACUAAAUUCAUGGAAGUAAAUGAUGUAUCUGUUCCUAAGUCACCCUAUCUGCUGAGUUACUUGUGACAAAUUGUUUAAACAGUAAAAGAAUUUAAUAUGAAAAGAUACACGUUAAGAUGAUUCUAGGAUUAAUUCAUUCAGGCAUGACAGCAUCACCAAGGACCCAGGUUCUUUCUAUCUUUUAAUGCUGCUGCUGUUCUUGAUCUGUUGGGUUGUCCUCAUGGUCCAGUUCUUGUUUACACAUUCAAACCCAGAAUUGCAUGCAAAAAGGCUGGGAGCAUGUGUUUUUACCUGGGUCUUUUUUCAUCAGCCAAGAAAACUUUUCCUAAAAGCUCCCUAGCAAACUUACUUUCUUGUCUUCUUGGCCAGAAUUGCAUUAGGAAUGUGUUACCAGACUACCCACUGGCAAGGGGAAUGGAAAUUGUCACAGUUGGUUCAGACCAGAGCUUUCUAGCCCAAGUAUUUUUUUCUGUUAUCUCUUCUGGAAGAAGCCUUUUCCCCUUGCCUUUUGAGUCUCUUCUGUAGUUCAGACUUAUGAAAAUAUGCAUCAGUUUAAUACUGUCUUGGAAUUCAUGAGAUGGAAGCAUAGGUCAAAGCUGUUUGGAGAAAAUCAGAAGUACAGUUUUAUCUAGCCACAUCUUGGAGGAGUCGUAAGAAAGCAGUGGGAGUUGAAGUCAUUGUCAAGUGCUUGCGAUCUUUUACAAGAAAAUCUCACUGAAUGAUAGUCAUUUAAAUUGGUGAAGUAGCAAGACCAAUUAUUAAAGGUGACAGUACACAGGAAACAUUACAAUUGAACAAUGCCUCAGCUAUACAUUUACAUCAGAUUAUUGGGAGCCUAUUUGUUCAUCAUUUCUCGUGUUCAAGGACAGAAUCUGGAUAGUAUGCUUCAUGGCACUGGGAUGAAAUCAGACUCCGACCAGAAAAAGUCAGAAAAUGGAGUAACCUUAGCACCAGAGGAUACCUUGCCUUUUUUAAAGUGCUAUUGCUCAGGGCACUGUCCAGAUGAUGCUAUUAAUAACACAUGCAUAACUAAUGGACAUUGCUUUGCCAUCAUAGAAGAAGAUGACCAGGGAGAAACCACAUUAGCUUCAGGGUGUAUGAAAUAUGAAGGAUCUGAUUUUCAGUGCAAAGAUUCUCCAAAAGCCCAGCUACGCCGGACAAUAGAAUGUUGUCGGACCAAUUUAUGUAACCAGUAUUUGCAACCCACACUGCCCCCUGUUGUCAUAGGUCCGUUUUUUGAUGGCAGCAUUCGAUGGCUGGUUUUGCUCAUUUCUAUGGCUGUCUGCAUAAUUGCUAUGAUCAUCUUCUCCAGCUGCUUUUGUUACAAACAUUAUUGCAAGAGCAUCUCAAGCAGACGUCGUUACAAUCGUGAUUUGGAACAGGAUGAAGCAUUUAUUCCAGUUGGAGAAUCACUAAAAGACCUUAUUGACCAGUCACAAAGUUCUGGUAGUGGGUCUGGACUACCUUUAUUGGUUCAGCGAACUAUUGCCAAACAGAUUCAGAUGGUCCGGCAAGUUGGUAAAGGCCGAUAUGGAGAAGUAUGGAUGGGCAAAUGGCGUGGCGAAAAAGUGGCGGUGAAAGUAUUCUUUACCACUGAAGAAGCCAGCUGGUUUCGAGAAACAGAAAUCUACCAAACUGUGCUAAUGCGCCAUGAAAACAUACUUGGUUUCAUAGCGGCAGACAUUAAAGGUACAGGUUCCUGGACUCAGCUCUAUUUGAUUACUGAUUACCAUGAAAAUGGAUCUCUCUAUGACUUCCUGAAAUGUGCUACACUGGACACCAGAGCCCUGCUUAAAUUGGCUUAUUCAGCUGCCUGUGGUCUGUGCCACCUGCACACAGAAAUUUAUGGCACCCAAGGAAAGCCCGCAAUUGCUCAUCGAGACCUAAAGAGCAAAAACAUCCUCAUCAAGAAAAAUGGGAGUUGCUGCAUUGCUGACCUGGGCCUUGCUGUUAAAUUCAACAGUGACACAAAUGAAGUUGAUGUGCCCUUGAAUACCAGGGUGGGCACCAAACGCUACAUGGCUCCCGAAGUGCUGGACGAAAGCCUGAACAAAAACCACUUCCAGCCCUACAUCAUGGCUGACAUCUACAGCUUCGGCCUAAUCAUUUGGGAGAUGGCUCGUCGUUGUAUCACAGGAGGGAUCGUGGAAGAAUACCAAUUGCCAUAUUACAACAUGGUACCGAGUGAUCCGUCAUACGAAGAUAUGCGUGAGGUUGUGUGUGUCAAACGUUUGCGGCCAAUUGUGUCUAAUCGGUGGAACAGUGAUGAAUGUCUACGAGCAGUUUUGAAGCUAAUGUCAGAAUGCUGGGCCCACAAUCCAGCCUCCAGACUCACAGCAUUGAGAAUUAAGAAGACGCUUGCCAAGAUGGUUGAAUCCCAAGAUGUAAAAAUCUGAUGGUUAAACCAUCGGAGGAGAAACUCUAGACUGCAAGAACUGUUUUUACCCAUGGCAUGGGUGGAAUUAGAGUGGAAUAAGGAUGUUAACUUGGUUCUCAGACUCUUUCUUCACUACGUGUUCACAGGCUGCUAAUAUUAAACCUUUCAGUACUCUUAUUAGGAUACAAGCUGGGAACUUCUAAACACUUCAUUCUUUAUAUAUGGACAGCUUUAUUUUAAAUGUGGUUUUUGAUGCCUUUUUUUAAGUGGGUUUUUAUGAACUGCAUCAAGACUUCAAUCCUGAUUAGUGUCUCCAGUCAAGCUCUGGGUACUGAAUUGCCUGUUCAUAAAACGGUGCUUUCUGUGAAAGCCUUAAGAAGAUAAAUGAGCGCAGCAGAGAUGGAGAAAUAGACUUUGCCUUUUACCUGAGACUUUCAGUUCGUUUGUAUUCUACCUUUGUAAAACAGCCUAUAGAUGAUGAUGUGUUUGGGAUACUGCUUAUUUUAUGAUAGUUUGUCCUGUGUCCUUAGUGAUGUGUGUGUGUCUCCAUGCACAUGCACGCCGGGAUUCCUCUGCUGCCAUUUGAAUUAGAAGAAAAUAAUUUAUAUGCAUGCACAGGAAGAUAUUGGUGGCCGGUGGUUUUGUGCUUUAAAAAUGCAAUAUCUGACCAAGAUUCGCCAAUCUCAUACAAGCCAUUUACUUUGCAAGUGAGAUAGCUUCCCCACCAGCUUUAUUUUUUAACAUGAAAGCUGAUGCCAAGGCCAAAAGAAGUUUAAAGCAUCUGUAAAUUUGGACUGUUUUCCUUCAACCACCAUUUUUUUUGUGGUUAUUAUUUUUGUCACGGAAAGCAUCCUCUCCAAAGUUGGAGCUUCUAUUGCCAUGAACCAUGCUUACAAAGAAAGCACUUCUUAUUGAAGUGAAUUCCUGCAUUUGAUAGCAAUGUAAGUGCCUAUAACCAUGUUCUAUAUUCUUUAUUCUCAGUAACUUUUAAAAGGGAAGUUAUUUAUAUUUUGUGUAUAAUGUGCUUUAUUUGCAAAUCACCCACUCCUUUACAACCAUACUUUAUAUAUGUACAUACAUUCAUACUGUAGAAACCAGCUCAUGUGUACCUCAUAUCCCAUCCUUAAGAGAAGAAAUGUUAUAAAGUAGAACUAAAUAUAAAUUUUCAGAAUUAAUGCAUUCAAAGUAAUAUAUCAAAUCCAGGACUUUGUUAACUUCAGGUAAAAACUUCAUUAGGGUAAUAUCAUCUCAAUUUUUUCAAAUGAAAGGAUUCUCUAAUUAGAAAUUUAUAUGUCAGAGCUGUUAUAAAUUUAUCAACUGUCAAAUAUGUUCUGGACAGCUAAAUCAUUUGAGAUUUUUGGUUUUUUGAUUUCUAUUCCCUAACUUGUGAAGACAAUGAAAAAUCAGGCAGAAAUAUUUAGUAUCUAGUCAGUAUCUGUAGCUACACUGUAUAACUGUUCUUCAAUAAAAUGGUUCAUAUUUUAUAGAUGCCUUGUUAUCUCAAGAAAUCUGAUUUACAUAAACUUAUACUUCUUUAAUGCUUUUUAAAUAUUUAUUCUGAGCAAACAAUUCAUGAGUACAUCAAGUGAGAUAGUUUUAUUUGAUUAUAACAUAAAAUAAAUGUGAUUAUAUCACAUCAUCAUCAAAAAGGUUUAAAUUAAAUGGGAGGAAAUCAGCAUAUGUCCACCCAUUACCAAAAUUUGACUAUCAUUUAAGGUUAAAACUUACAAAUUUGUCUGCACAUCAAAUUUCACAAAUUUGAAAAUUGCCUUAACCAUUUUGAUUAAUAAGUUUCAUCUGCCAUAAUUAAAGUCUGAAGUGUUCAUCAAGAUAAGUAAAUUUGCAUAUGGAUAAUACCCAAUAACUUGUUUUUUCAGAAUUUUUCACCAUAUGUAUACUGAGAAAUACAAAUAUUUUAAUCUGCGUUGCCGUAUGAUAUGAUUGCACUUAGAACACCCAAUUUACUUAAAUCUUGGUUUACUUUUGACUUGAUACCAUAAUCUUUAAAAUCAUUUGUCAUCUUUUUUUUUUUUUUUUUGAGACGGAGUCUCGCUCUGUCGCCCAGGCUGGACUGCGGACUGCAGUGGCGCAAUCUCGGCUCACUGCAAGCUCCGCUUCCCGGGUUCACGCCAUUCUCCUGCCUCAGCCUCCCGAGUAGCUGGGACUACAGGCGCCCGCCACCGCGCCCGGCUAAUUUUUUGUAUUUUUAGUAGAGACGGGGUUUCACCUUGUUAGCCAGGAUGGUCUCAAUCUCCUGACCUCAUGAUCCACCUGCCUCGGCCUCCCAAAGUUCAUUUGUCAUCUUAAUAAAAAUAUAAAGACAGGCAAAGUUUAUUGGAAAUGUUCAAAUGGUGUGUGGAAGCAAAAAAUUACAGCCAGUAUAUGAGACCACUAUUAUGGUUUUUUAAAAUUAACUUGGUCUAGUAAAAGUGAUAUCAAGAGUUAAUCUUAGAAACUUGCUCAGUAAAAACAUUUUCUAGUAUAACAUGUUCUUUAAAAAGCAAAUGCUGCCGUCUUUGGAAUCUUAAUCUAAAAAUGUGGCCGGGCGCGGUGGCUCACGCCUGUAAUCCCAACACUUUGGGAGGCUGAGGCGGGUGGAUCACAAGGUCAGGAGUUCAAGACCAGCCUGGCCAACAUGGUGAAACCCCAUCUCUACUAAAAAUAAAAAACUCAGCCAGGCGUGGUGGCGGGUGCCUGUAAUCCCAGCUACUCGGGAGGCUGAAGCAGGAGAAUUGCUUAAAAUCAGAAGGUGGAGGUUGCAGUGAGCUGAGAUCGUGUCACUGCACUCCAGCCUGGGCAAAAGAGCGAAACUCCAUCUCAAAUAAACAAACAAAUAAAUAACAAAAAACAAAAAUGUUGCAUUAAACUUAGUUCUUGUCUCUCCUUUCCACUCUUAUUCUUAAAUCUGAAGCUCAUCGACUAAGUGAAAUAUUUAAAGAAUAUGAUAGGCCAGCAAGAAGAAGUAUUAUGUAGUACCAUAGUUAGUAAAUUCGUAAAACCUUGGAAGCCAUUAUUUGGUCCCACUUGCAAUUUAGUGUUUUUGAAGUGUGUAGCUUCAUUCAGAUAGCUCUUUAAAUAAUUAAAAUAUAAAAGCAAACAACCCAAACUACCUGACUAUAAACAGGAAAAGUUAACCCUCAAAGAGAGUUCUUGUGAAUUCUCUUUAUGCUGGCAAAUAGCUCUAGGAUUAAAGGCACAUUAGGGUUUCCUUCAGUUUGUUUAUUCUAAGCUUUUACUGUGCUUUUUACUGAACAAGUUUCUGAUGUAUAAAACUUGCAUCUGAUUUCUUUGGAAAUAUUUUCACAAAAGUUAUUUUAAUCAGUAUUUUUACAUUGCCUUUCCAGUGUCCAGAAGUGUUUCUAAACUUAGAAAGUGACCUAUAGUUUUUUAAAAUUAUGUUUUCCUAGAACGUGCCAAAUUUUGAUUUACUCUAACAAUCAGUACUUUUCUUCAGAUGCUUUGUUCUGUUUAGAACAAAAAUGCACUAUAGUUUUUAAAGAAUCAUGCAUCUUUGGGUUGGCCCAGGAUCAAAUUUGAUAUUGAAUAAUUUAUUCCAGGGCAGCUUUCAUAAACAUACUUCAUAGAUGUUGUUUUGAAAUGUUUCUAAAUAUCUAAAAUCAUUUCAACAGCAGAAAUGAUUUUUAUUUUAACAAAAGAUUAUGAUAGCCCUUGUAGUGUUUAAAAGUGGUCAUAUUUAUUACUGACUUUGAGUCAGGUGUUAAAAUAGCAGUGCCACAGCUCGUCUCUUGCCUUAGUGUGCUGCUGUGAGAGUCACAGUGGAAACUGCAGGGAGGAGGUGUGUUCCUAAGAACCAAAAUCCAGCACAGCAUCCUGUGAAGCCACGUGUAAUGAUGGUCCCAUAAGGAAAGUAUGUGAAUAUGGCUCUUGUAAAGGAUUAACUAUUGUAAUUUUAGCUUAUGCUCUGUAUUCUGUUUUCUAUGGAAUUAUUUAAGCCCUUUUAGUGACCUUUGUCCUGGCCCAUUUAAAAACUAAAAUGUAGUAUAUAUUGUAUAAAAUGGAAAUAUCAUUAUUGCUUCAUUAGGGGAAACUGUACAUAGGCAUUGAAAGAAGGGUAAAAGCAAGCAGUUUUAUCAGGCAGUUGUAAAACACCAAAAAUAUAGAUUCGUCUUUGACGUGUAACACACUAAAUGUAUUUUGUACAGCAUCUGGUUUAAAAGGUGCCUUAAGAGUUUACCAUUACUUGCUUUGUUCUAUAUACAGAUUAUGUCCAAUGUAUCAUUUUGAAGUAAAUAACCUUAUUUUAGUAUA